CGCCGGGGGCCGUGGACAGGGCAGCUCGCAAGUCGGCCUUGCUGGGCCUUGGUUUACUCACCUGUAAAGUGGGAAUGACCUGGCUUCCCACUGUGGGUAUUGGGAUGUGGUUGGCGAGUGGGAUUUCCACGAUGGCUGCCCCCAAGGUCCUGCUUACGCUACUCCACUCCACCCUGCCACAGCCGUCACCGAGUCCCCGUACUGUCCUCAUACCCCCUCCUCCAUGCACCCUGUCCCCCUGCACUUUCCUGACCGCCCCUACCUGCUGAGGUCUGUGUGGGCUGCCACCCUCUACACCCCAGGUUCCCCAUCUGAAAUGAAAUUGGAAGACCAUCUCGCUGGACUACGUGGGUGGGGGCGGUUAAGGGUGGGCAUUUGUAAAGUGCUGAGCACCGCCCGUCCAGUCUUAACCAUUCACACCCUUGCCCAUUUCUCAAAACCUGUGCUAGCCACAGUUCAUGUUCACUGAGCACCUGCCCUGUGUUGAGCUCUGAGGACGCGGGCAGGCUGCACGUUUCAUCUCCUGAAGUGGGAGCUGCUGUGGCUUCCAUCUGUAGACCGGGAAACUGAGCACAGAGAGUGGAGUGACUUGCUCGAGGUCACACAGCAAGGACGCAGCAGCUGUCAGCCUGCCUGGCCGUGGGUUGGCCUGCUCCAGCUGUUGGCAUCACUGGGCAGAGAGAGGGUCCCCAGAGAGGCUAGGGGGGUUCUUUGCUAGCCCCGGGCAUGGGGAGAAAGCAGCAGAGAGCAGCUGUGGCUCACAGAUGCCCCCAGCCACUGGGGGCCCAAGUGCUCUGUCGCCCACCUGGAGAGUCCCCACGGACCCCAGGUGGGCCACAGACGAGACCGGUGCUGACUUAGGGGCUCGGUGGGGACCAGGCAGCUGCUCUCAGACACCGAGGCAGGCCCAGGGCAGCAUCCACCUCGACACAUCCUAUUUGUGGGCUGACAGUUGUCUCCUGCAUUAUCAGAGCCGUUUUAAUUGUGCUGGAACUGAAAUUAGCCUGGCAGCCUCUUUCUCCACGCUCAUCACCACGGCUUUGUGUGGAGCAGGAGCCUUUGUUCUUGUGUAAAUAGGAGAACCCAUCACCAUCCCAGCACCUCCCUGGGUGUCUGAGGCCCACCUGGGUGGGGUAUGGAGAGCCAGCCCACCUUCCUGAGGCUGCAGCAGGUAUGCACAGGGCUGUGUCUCCUGUGGGCCCCAGCCCCAGUGCUCUGGUCCCCGAAGUCCCUGAAGGCAGGUGGCCUCCAGCCCAUUUGCCAGAGCAGGUCACUGAGGCCCUGAUGCCCUACAGCUGCUCAGCAGGAGGAAGCACAGCUCCUGGGCAGCCCCUCCCAGCUCCAUGCCAGCCACAGAAAGCCCGGGCCUCUAGAAGGGGGAGGAGCCGGGCUGAGCUGAUCGUUCCGCGUGCUCCCGCCAAGUCGGGGAUGGCCGAGCACCUCCUGACCUUCUGGAUGGCACUGCCUGCUCAGGGCCGACCCCAGAGGUGGGGAGGGGAGGCCUCGGUGGCUGCUUUUCUGCCCUGGCGUGUGCUGAGGGAGGGCACUCGGGUUGGGCCUCCUGUCCCAGGGGCAGGAGUUGAACCGGUCAGGGGUGGCCCAGCCUGCCCUGGAGCCUGCCCGUGUGGGCGCUUUAAUGGGAGGCUGUGAGCCCUCGCCUGGGGCUGGCUCCUGUGUGGUCUGAGCCCAGCCCCCUCCUAUAAUUACAGCUCUGAGGUGCUCUGAGGAGGCCGGGACUCAUGGGUCCCAGCUAGAGCCCCAAAGGCUGCAGCUAGGAGAGUCCAGCCUGCCCCUCCUGUCCAGGACCCCCCAUGGCUCCCCGGUGGCACCUGCCCCUCCUGUCCAGGACCCCCCAUGGCUCCCCGGUGGCCCCAGGAUGAGGGUCCCCUCCUCCCCGUGGCCUCUGAGGUCAGCACGGCCAGGACCCUGCCUGCCCUCAGCCUUGACUGCCAGCACACCCUGGCCCCCGACCUCCCCUUCCUCCACCACCUCUGGCCCCGCCCCAGGGCCUUUGCACAUAUGGCCCCCUCUGCCAGAGCUGUCUUCUCAGGGGCUGGUCUCACAACAACCACUGUUCCCUCCGAGAUCUACCGGCGGCAGCCCCUCCCAUCCCCGUGUUUUUCUGUCUUUCUCUCAUGGCCCCUUCCCUCACUGCACUUCCAGAACUUGCCAUUGUUUUCGGCCGGGGCCCAUCUGUUGUUCUCUGACUGUCCCCACAGUGGCCCGGACACCCAGGGCAGUGUUCAGCGAUCUGGUGCACCCCUGCAUCCUGGAACGGCACCUGGCACCUAGCCCUCGGGUGUCAGCAGAAGGCAGAAAAGGCAUCUGCCCCUCCAGGAGCAGUUUGGUUUGACGGCAUCAGCCAGCCACAGCCUGCUCAUGAUCAGAGAGGGGGCUGGAGUCCAAACGCGCAGAAAAUCCACCUUCCCGCCUCCCUGCUGCAUGGAACGGCGGGGUCAGCCUUGGACAUCAGCCUGAAACUCAGUCACAGCAUUUCUCCUUCUCUCGCAUCUUCGGGGGUCUCUGACAUGAGCCUCUGAACCUGGCGUUGGACGCUGGCGGGUGGCACGUUUCUUACUGGCUGGGCAGGUGUUUCGGGCGUUAGCAGGCUCCACCUCCGACCAGCCCAUCUCCCUCCCAUCUUCUGCCUUUCCCUGGAGAAACAAAGCAAAGCAGGGAUCAUGAGGGGCUGUGAAGGAGGACAGUGGGGAUUCGGAGAGAAGCUCUUGAAGCUGGGCACAUGUGGGCGCUUCGGUGUGUUUUUCUGGGGAGGAGGCACCAGGUUUCAUCAGAUUCCCAGAGGGGCCAUGAGGCAAGACAAGCCAGGAACCACCUAGCCAGAGGCGCAAACCCCGAACAGUUCUCCAUCCGUGCGGCUUGCUUGCCUCCAGGGAUGGGGCGCUCAGCCCUCAGGAGGUGGUUGUUCCAGCCUGCAACGCUCAGGCCUUCCCUCUGGUGUCUUCUGUUCUGCCCCACCCCCACUCUGCCCCAUCAGCUCCCCUGACACGUGAACUCAGACACGCGGUUUCCAGACUUUUCUUAUUCAUUAUUCUGCUGUGACCAUGGGGCUUGGCGGCCGCAGGACCUGGGGUCUGGGCUCAGGAGGGCCACGGCCCCUCCCACUCCUGAGUGUGUCGGGAGGCUCUGCCCCCAUCGUGCUUCACACAGGACAGUAGAAGGCUGGGCGGGUCAGGCCUUGUGGAGUAUGGGUGCAGAGGGGGCAGUCGCAGCACGCAGGCUGAGUCAGGGCCUGGGGACCUGGGGAGCAGUCAAACAGGAUAUGGAAGGGCACCUCUGUCCUCUGUUCACACUGGACACCAUCACCCAUCACCAGCCCCGCCGGCGGAUGUCAGCACACACACCUGCACUCAGCGCCACUCCACAGCCACUGUGGGGUCCGGAGCAGCUGCCCCCGCACUUGGGCCGCGUGGCCUUGUCUCAGUCUGCCUUGUCACCUGUCAGGUGGACUCCUGGAGUUCCCCCACCCCGAUGUGUGAGUCUCUGAGGGACCCAGGCCCUGAGGCACUCCACCCCCAGGUGCUGCAGACACCUGUGCCCUGCUUGGUUUGUUCGCUCGACAAGUCUGUGAGCGCCUCCUUUGUGCUGGGUGAGGGUGUCACCCCAGGGAGUUCCCAGACCGAGGGAAUGAGUGUGAGGGAAGUGCACGGGGACUGGGCCCCUGGGCGGGGCACUGGCAGGUGAUGCCAGGCGGAGGCCGUGGCGACGGCGACCCUCAGGGCCUGGAUGGACGCUGGGCCUACAGUACAGGGAGGGCCCACUCGCAGCUCCAGGGCUGCCAGAGCAGGUGGGGGCCUGUCCCCUGGUGCUGGGGGGAGCAGGUGGGAAAGAGACACGGGGUCCGCGGCCCUUCUCUGGCAAGAGUGGAAUCCGUGGGCGUGGUGGAGGCCAAGGGUCACGGCAGGUUCCCUCGGAGACAUGGAGGCCAGAGAGGAGGUGCAGUUGGUGGGUGCCAGCCACAUGGAGCAAAAGGCCACGGCACCUGAAGCCCCGAGCCCUCCCAGCGCAGAUGUUAACUCACCCCCACCGCUGCCGCCCCCCACAUCCCCAGGAGGCCCCAAGGAGCUGGAAGGACAGGAACCAGAACCCAGGCCCACGGAGGAAGAGCCGGGCAGUCCCUGGAGCGGGCCAGACGAGCUGGAGCCGGUGGUGCAGGAUGGGCAGAGGCGCAUACGGGCCCGACUCAGCCUCGCCACGGGCCUGUCCUGGGGCCCGUUCCAUGGGAGUGUCCAGACCAGAGCCUCAUCCCCCAGGCAGGCGGAGCCGAGCCCAGCCCUGACCCUGCUGCUGGUGGACGAGGCCUGCUGGCUGAGGACGCUGCCCCAGGCCCUGACUGAGGCCGAGGCCAACACAGAGAUCCACAGGAAGGAUGACGCACUCUGGUGCAGGGUCACCAAGCCGGUGCCUGCGGGGGGACUCCUGAGCGUGCUCCUCACGGCCGAGCCCCACAGCACCCCCGGCCACCCUGUGAAGAAGGAGCCAGCAGAGCCCACGUGCCCGGCCCCUGCACACGACCUCCAGCUCCUGCCCCAGCAGGCCGGGAUGGCCUCCAUCCUUGCCACCGCAGUGAUCAACAAAGACGUCUUCCCCUGCAAGGACUGUGGCAUCUGGUACCGCAGCGAGCGCAACCUGCAGGCGCACCUGCUCUACUACUGCGCCAGCCGCCAGGGCACCGGCUCCCCGGCCGCAGCCGCCACAGACGAGAAGCCCAAAGAGACCUACCCCAACGAGCGCGUCUGCCCCUUCCCCCAGUGCCGCAAGAGCUGCCCCAGCGCCAGCUCCCUGGAGAUCCACAUGCGCAGCCACAGCGGAGAGCGGCCCUUCGUGUGCCUGAUCUGCCUGUCGGCCUUCACCACCAAGGCCAACUGCGAGCGGCACCUCAAGGUGCACACGGACACGCUGAGCGGUGUCUGCCACAGCUGUGGCUUCAUCUCCACCACAAGGGACAUCCUCUACAGCCACUUGGUCACCAACCACAUGGUCUGCCAGCCUGGCUCCAAGGGUGAGAUCUACUCGCCAGGGGCCGGACACCCAGCAACCAAGCUGCCCCCAGACAGUCUGGGCAGCUUCCAGCAGCAGCACACGGCCCUGCAAGGCCCCCUGGCCUCCGCGGACCUGGGCCUGGCGCCCACCCCAUCGCCAGGACUGGACAGAAAGGCCCUGGCCGAGGCCACCAACGGAGAGGCCAGAGCGGAGCCUCUGGCCCAGAAUGGAGGCAGCAGCGAGCCCCCGGCGGCCCCCAGGAGCAUCAAGGUGGAGGCGGUGGAGGAGCCGGAGGCGGCCCCCAUCCUGGGCCCCGGAGAGCCUGGGCCCCAGGCCCCGUCGCGGACGCCGUCGCCGCGCAGCCCCGCCCCGGCCAGGGUCAAGGCCGAGCUGUCCAGCCCCACGCCGGGCUCCAGCCCGGUGCCCGGCGAGCUGGGCCUGGCCGGGGCCCUGUUCCUUCCGCAGUACGUGUUCGGGCCCGACGCGGCGCCCCCCGCCUCGGAGAUCCUGGCCAAGAUGUCCGAGCUGGUGCACAGCCGGCUGCAGCAGGGCGCGGGCGCGGGCGCCGGCGGCGCGCAGACCGGGCUCUUCCCCGGGGCCCCCAAGGGCGCUACGUGCUUCGAGUGCGAGAUCACCUUCAGCAACGUCAACAACUACUACGUGCACAAGCGCCUCUACUGUUCAGGCCGCCGUGCGCCCGAGGACGCGCCUGCCGCGCGCAGGCCCAAGGCGCCCCCCGGCCCGGCCCGCGCGCCCCCCGGCCAGCCCGCCGAACCCGACGCGCCGCGCUCGUCCCCGGGCCCCGGAGCGCGCGAGGAGGGGGCUGGGGGCGCGGCCACGCCCGAGGACGGCGCGGGCGGCCGGGGCAGCGAGGGCAGCCAGAGCCCGGGUAGCUCCGUGGACGACGCGGAGGACGACCCCAGCCGCACGCUGUGCGAGGCCUGCAACAUCCGCUUCAGCCGCCACGAGACCUACACCGUGCACAAGCGGUACUACUGCGCCUCGCGCCACGACCCGCCGCCGCGCCGACCGGCCGCGCCCCCGGGACCCCCUGGGCCGGCCGCGCCCCCGGCCCCCUCUCCCGCCGCGCCUGUGCGCACGCGCAGACGCCGCAAGCUCUACGAGCUGCACGCGGCCGGCGCCCCGCCCCCCCCGCCGCCCGGCCACGCCCCCGCGCCCGAGUCGCCGCGGCCCGGAAGCGGAAGCGGAAGCGGCCCCGGCCUCGCCCCUGCGCGCUCGCCCGGCCCCGCGGCCGACGGCCCCAUCGACCUGAGCAAGAAGCCGCGGCGCCCGCUCCCCGGAGCCCCGGCACCGGCGCUGGCCGACUACCACGAGUGCACGGCCUGCCGCGUGAGCUUCCACAGCCUCGAGGCCUACCUGGCGCACAAGAAGUACUCGUGCCCCGCUGCGCCACCGCCCGGCGCGCUCGGCCUGCCCGCCGCCGCCUGCCCCUACUGCCCCCCGAACGGCCCGGUGCGCGGGGACCUGCUGGAGCAUUUCCGCCUGGCGCACGGCCUGCUGCUCGGCGCGCCCCUGGCCGGCCCGGGGGUCGAGGCCCGGACGCCGGCCGACCGCGGCCCCUCGCCCGCUCCCGCCCCCGCCGCCUCCCCGCAGCCCGGGUCCCGUGGCCCCCGGGACGGCCUCGGCCCGGAGCCCCAGGAGCCGCCGCCCGGCCCGCCCCCGUCCCCGGCCGCCGCGCCCGAGGCCGUGCCGCCCCCGCCGGCGCCCCCCUCCUACUCGGACAAGGGCGUCCAGACUCCCAGCAAGGGCACGCCGGCGCCGCUGCCCAACGGCAACCACCGGUACUGCCGUCUUUGCAACAUCAAGUUCAGCAGCCUGUCCACCUUCAUCGCCCACAAGAAGUAUUACUGCUCCUCGCACGCCGCCGAGCACGUGAAGUGAGCGCCCACACUACAGCCGCAGACGCUUUGCACGCCCCGCUGCGAUGCGGGGAGGGGGCCGCCCCCAGGCCGCACGGACUGCCGCUCCUGGGAACCCCGCCACGCACAGGCCUCGGCGGAGGGGGCCGCAGGGGGCAGCGCCCGCCUGGACCCUUGGCACUUAAUAAAGAAGUUCAGUUUGAUGAGCAUGGUGGUGGGCCAGCCUAGUUCUCUGAGCCAGCAGGCACACGCAGCCAGUGUCACAUCCAGCCCUGCUGUGUACACAGGCCACUGCGGCCCGGAGUGGCUGGGCCCCUGCCGGAGUUACACCACUGGGUGCUAAGAGCUAGACCGAGCGUCAGGUCGGAGGCCACAGCACACACUGAACCACUGCAGGGCCAGCCGCUCUGGGCCUACCCCACCCCAGCCCUGUCCAUACCCCCCUAGGGAGAGCAGCCUCCACACUGCUGACCCUCUCCACGGUCUACUUGGCCGCCAGACACGGAAGAGAGGGGCACUGACCUGGCUGGCCAUCCCCCAACCCUGCAUGGUCCUGGGGGUCCGAUGUCCCCCAUCCAGUCACAGACCACCAGGGAUGGCAGGGGUGGGGGCGCCCUGGGGAGGAUGAAGCCCUGUGGUGGCCAAGGCUGGGGGAAGAACAGGCGAGUAGGUGGACAGGAGAGGGAGACCGAGGCCGAAGCAUUCCCUGGCCUCGAGGGGGUCCUGAUGCUCACUGGUGGGUGCAUCUCUCCCUCAGAGCCAGGGCUGAGGACAACCGUGUGGUGGAGUCACCUGUGGUGGCUGAGUCGGUGCAAGGGUCAGGGCACCCCCACCCCCCGUCUUCCCUGCCCUGCUGGGCUGUAUGGGCCGGCCACACUGAGGGAGUACUUGGCUGACCGCGUUCAGCCACGGUGUCACCGUGCCGUUUGCAGCUGGGUGGCUGUGGGCAGCCUCCAGCGUGCUUUCUCACUGGAGAACAAAAACACUCUUCUAUUCCCAACGUCACUUUAUUUUUUUAUUUUUGGGUCUCACUCUCUUGCCCAGGCUGGAGUCCCUGGGAUACUCACGGCUCAUUGCAGCCUUGACCUCGUGAGCUCAAGUGAUCUUCCCACCUCAGUUUCCUCAGUAGCUGGGGCUACAGGUGUACACCACCAUGCCCAGCUAGUUUUUGUGUUUUUUGUAGAAAUGGUGUCUCCCUAUGUUGCCCAGGCUGGGCAACCCUAUAUUUUUUAGAGCUAAGGUCUUGUUCGGUUCCCCAGGCUGAAGUUCAGUGGCACGAUCAUAAGUCACUGCAGCCUCAAACUCCUGAGCUGAAACCAUCUUCCUGCCUCAGCCUCCCAAGUAGCUGGGACUACAGGCUUGACCCACCACACCUGGCUAACUUUUAAAACAUUUUUAUAGAGACAGGGUCUUCCUGUGUUGCCCAAGAUGGUCUCAAACUCCUGACCUCCAGUGCUCCUGCAGCCUCAGCCUCCCAGAACAUUAGGAUGACAGGCGCGAGCUACCAUUCCCAGCCCAUUUCCAACUCUACUUGAACUAGCUGCAUUUUUUUCAGCUUUGCCCAGCAGCCCUGGUGAGUGCAGGCAAAGAAGGCAGCGGCCUCUUGCCUCAGAAGCCCGAGGCACUUCCCAGCCAGUCCAGGGCUCGCUCUCCUGCCCGCAGCUCGUGGGCCUGGGUCUGCAGCGCUUUCAGUGGUCUCUGAUGUCUUUGUCCACCUGCCCACUAGGGUCUGGCCAGAUGGGGCCCGUAGCCAAGGCCAAUGGACAGACAUGGCUUCCACCCCCUCCCAGGGACCUGAGCUCCAGGGAAGGCAAGCAGCCUUUUCCUCACAGACACCCCUUCUGUUGAAGACCAGGUGAUAGCGGGGACGGGAGGCACGGACCCCUCAAGUCUGCUCAUCAUUUGCAUUGUUGUGCAUGAAUUUGCGUGGAGGGUUCAGGAGGCUCUGCCCCCAAGUCCUCCCCAGGUGCGGGCGCAGGGUACAAGAUGUUCUAAAAAAUAGAAACCUGGUGGGGGGUUGUCACUGUGUGUACAUUUAAAAGUAAACUGUUUAAAGGUGUCUAGAAACUACGAA